GUGUCUCCAUAGCAACCGCUCCAUCUGAUUGCCCCUCCCCGCUCCCAGAGGCCACCUAGUGCGCAGGCCCGCCUGAUGUCGUCCCACGCCGUGCCGGCUCUCAGGCGCCGGAAGUGAGCUGCGCAGCGCCGGAAGCGGCGGACGCAGGAGGCCUCGUGGAGGACACAGCAGCAUGGGACAGUCAGGGAGGGUAAGGCCCGGCAGCUUGGGAGGCAGGUGGCGCAGGUGGGGUCCCGGCCGAGGUCGCGGCGCUGACCCUUUGUCUCUCGUCGCCGCAGUCCCGGCACCAGAAGCGCGCCCGCGCCCAGGCGCAGCUCCGCAACCUCGAGGCCUAUGCCGCGAACCCGCACUCGUUCGUGUUCACGCGAGGCUGCACGGGUCGCAACAUCCGGCAGCUCAGCCUGGACGUGCGGCGGGUCAUGGAGCCGCUCACUGCCAGCCGUCUGCAGGUUCGUAAGAAGAACUCGCUGAAGGACUGCGUGGCAGUGGCUGGGCCCCUCGGGGUCACACACUUUCUGAUCCUGAGCAAAACAGAGACCAAUGUCUACUUUAAGCUGAUGCGCCUCCCAGGAGGCCCCACCUUGACCUUCCAGGUCAAGAAGUACUCGCUGGUGCGUGAUGUGGUCUCCUCACUGCGCCGGCACCGCAUGCACGAGCAGCAGUUUGCCCACCCACCCCUCCUGGUACUCAACAGCUUUGGCCCCCAUGGUAUGCAUGUGAAGCUCAUGGCCACCAUGUUCCAGAACCUGUUCCCCUCCAUCAACGUGCACAAGGUGAACCUGAACACCAUCAAGCGCUGCCUCCUCAUCGACUACAACCCCGACUCCCAGGAGCUGGACUUCCGCCACUAUAGCAUCAAAGUUGUUCCUGUGGGCGCGAGUCGCGGGAUGAAGAAGCUGCUCCAGGAGAAGUUCCCCAACAUGAGCCGCCUGCAGGACAUCAGCGAGCUGCUGGCCACGGGCGCGGGGCUGUCGGAGAGCGAGGCAGAGCCUGACGGCGACCACAACAUCACAGAGCUGCCUCAGGCUGUCGCUGGCCGUGGCAACAUGCGGGCCCAGCAGAGUGCAGUGCGGCUCACCGAGAUCGGCCCGCGGAUGACACUGCAGCUCAUCAAGGUCCAGGAGGGCGUCGGGGAGGGCAAAGUGAUGUUCCACAGUUUUGUGAGCAAGACGGAGGAGGAGCUGCAGGCCAUCCUGGAAGCCAAGGAGAAGAAGCUGCGGCUGAAGGCGCAGAGGCAGGCCCAGCAGGCCCAGAAUGUGCAGCGCAAGCAGGAGCAGCGGGAGGCCCACAGAAAGAAGAGCCUGGAGGGCAUGAAGAAGGCACGGGUCGGGGGUAGUGAUGAAGAGGCCUCUGGGAUCCCUUCAAGGACGGCGAGCCUGGAGUUGGGUGAGGACGAUGAUGAACAGGAAGAUGAUGACAUCGAGUAUUUCUGCCAGGCGGUGGGCGAGGCGCCCAGUGAGGACCUGUUCCCCGAGGCCAAGCAGAAACGGCUUGCCAAGUCUCCAGGGCGGAAGCGGAAGCGGUGGGAAAUGGAUCGAGGCAGGGGUCGCCUUUGUGACCAGAAGUUUCCCAAGACCAAGGACAAGUCCCAGGGAGCCCAGGCCAGGCGGGGGCCCAGAGGGGCUUCCCGGGAUGGUGGGCGAGGCCGGGGCCGGGGCCGCCCAGGGAAGAGAGUGGCCUGAGCCCAAGCCGCACCGGAGCAGCGGCUGGAUUGAACGCCCCAGAUUGGGGCCCGAGAUGUGGCCCUCGGUUUCCUUUCAUAAAGGAGUUGUGUCCCCAGCCCUUCCACUCCAGUAAAGAACUGAAUUGGCCAGGGGUCCACGUCAGCGUUUGGGAUGGGGGAUUCUGGAGCCAUACAAAGCAACCCAGAGAGUCCUGGGCCGGCCACACCCGAGAGUCCCUCCCACCUGGUUUCUUCCUGGAAGCUGGGUCUCUCCCCUACCCUGCACGGGGUUGGUUUCAUUGGUGGCAGCAGCAGCCAUGAGUGGCCCCUCCCCCCAGUCCCACCAAAGAGCCGUGCAAGCAGACAGGUCACACUUUCAGCAGAUGAGCUUGAACCUCAGGAGGGUUGUGGCACAAUGAGGAAGGAAACGUGGGUGGAAAGGCACGCUGGCCUGCUCUGCUGGCUGGGCCAGUAACUGGGGAUGGGGCUGGGGCAGGGCCCACUAAGCCACUGGUGACUGGGGGAGGGGCUGGGGAACUGGGUAGCAGACACAGGCUGAGGAUCGGCACGGGAGCAUGGCAGCCAACGUCUCGGGUAAGGAGAAGGCAUGUUGGCUGUCUCUGGGGGUCUGCAGAUUGUCAGGAGGUGGGGGUAGUGGGUAUUGGUAAAACACCUAGGUCUGGGGCUGGGCACGGUGGCUCACGCCUGUAAUCCCAGCACUUUGGGAGGUCGAGGGGGGUGGAACACGAGGUCAGGGGUUCGAGACCACCCUGACCAACAAGGAGAAACCCCGUCUCUACUAAAAAUAAAAAAAUUAGCUGGGCCUGGUGGCACAUGCCUGUAAUCCCAGCUACUCG